CGGCACCUGGAAAUGGAAAGCCAGUGAAGGCUGCUUUGGGCCGGGGCAGCGGGUGGGACCGGGCGGGAGGGAUUCCAAAGAGACCGCCGGGAAGGCUAGAGCUUGGAAUUCCGGCUCCUCGGAGUCCUGGCCCUCCCCCACCGCCGCCUCGGAGCUCAGCACACCUUGGAUGGGGGAGGCGGGCAGCUCCUAGCCCCGCACCCCAGGAGGCGCGCUCGGAGGGAAGCCGCCACCGCGCCGCCUCUGCCUCGGCGCGGAACAAACGGUUAAAGAUUUUGGGCAGCGCCUCGCGGGGGGAGGAGCCAGGGGCCCAAUCCGCAAUUAAAGAUGAACUUUGGGUGAACUAAUUGUCUGACCAAGCGGAGGAAGUUCCUGCAGAUGAAGCGCAGGAAAUACGGCUUCAUCUACAAGACGCAUCUGUUCGGGCGGCCCACCGUACGGGUGAUGGGCGCGGACAAUGUGCGGCGCAUCUUGCUCGGAGAGCACCGGCUGGUGUCGGUCCACUGGCCAGCGUCGGUGCGCACCAUUCUGGGAUCUGGCUGCCUCUCUAACCUGCACGACUCCUCGCACAAGCAGCGCAAGAAGGUGAUUAUGCGGGCCUUCAGCCGCGAGGCACUCGAAUGCUACGUGCCGGUGAUCACCGAGGAAGUGGGCAGCAGCCUGGAGCAGUGGCUGAGCUGCGGCGAGCGCGGCCUCCUGGUCUACCCCGAGGUGAAGCGCCUCAUGUUCCGAAUCGCCAUGCGCAUCCUACUGGGCUGCGAACCCCAACUGGCGGGCGACGGGGACUCCGAGCAGCAGCUUGUGGAGGCCUUCGAGGAAAUGACCCGCAAUCUCUUCUCGCUGCCCAUCGACGUGCCCUUCAGCGGGCUGUACCGGGGCAUGAAGGCGCGGAACCUCAUUCACGCGCGCAUCGAGCAGAACAUUCGCGCCAAGAUCUGCGGGCUGCGGGCAUCCGAGGCGGGCCAGGGCUGCAAAGACGCGCUGCAGCUGUUGAUCGAGCACUCGUGGGAGAGGGGAGAGCGGCUGGACAUGCAGGCACUAAAGCAAUCUUCAACCGAACUCCUCUUUGGAGGACACGAAACCACGGCCAGUGCAGCCACAUCUCUGAUCACUUACCUGGGGCUCUACCCACAUGUUCUCCAGAAAGUGCGAGAAGAGCUGAAGAGUAAGGGUUUACUUUGCAAGAGCAAUCAAGACAACAAGUUGGACAUGGAAAUUUUGGAACAACUUAAAUACAUCGGGUGUGUUAUUAAGGAGACCCUUCGACUGAAUCCCCCAGUUCCAGGAGGGUUUCGGGUUGCUCUGAAGACUUUUGAAUUAAAUGGAUACCAGAUUCCCAAGGGCUGGAAUGUUAUCUACAGUAUCUGUGAUACUCAUGAUGUGGCAGAGAUCUUCACCAACAAGGAAGAAUUUAAUCCUGACCGAUUCAUGCUGCCUCACCCAGAGGAUGCAUCCAGGUUCAGCUUCAUUCCAUUUGGAGGAGGCCUUAGGAGCUGUGUAGGCAAAGAAUUUGCAAAAAUUCUUCUCAAAAUAUUUACAGUGGAGCUGGCCAGGCAUUGUGACUGGCAGCUUCUAAAUGGACCUCCUACAAUGAAAACCAGUCCCACCGUGUAUCCUGUGGACAAUCUCCCUGCAAGAUUCACCCAUUUCCAUGGGGAAAUCUGAUGAGCUUGAAUGUUCAAACCUGAGACUUAUUGGAAGUGUACAUAUGAGUUUUUAAGGAGUGUUGUGUUGACUUUAUAUUUAAUUUCUAAAUGUAUAUUAUAAUAUUUAUGUGUUUUGACUAUACUACCACAAUCUUUAAAUAUUAAAAUAAUGAAUUUGUAUCAUUUCCAAAUAAAGUAAAAUUUGAAGGUACUUUUCUGGUAUUUUAAGAUUCCUGUUGGGUAAAACUCACCAGUUUAGUAUUUUCUUAGUGUAUUUAACCAGAUUUUACAAUGCCUACCUGGACUUAUUUGUCAUCUUUGCAUCUGUUUUCUGUGAGAAGAAAUCUUAGCUGUUUUUUAUGUUAACAGUUAUUAGAAAAUAUAUGUCUGUGUGUGUUAUUCCAGACGUAUCUCUGUAAAUUCUUCUACAGUCACUUAGAUUCCCUAUUUGGAAAAUUGAUCCAAGUUAAUUUAAUUUUUUUUUGGUUUGCUGUACUUUAGGGAAAGAUGAACCUGAAAAGGUAACACUGAGAACUGUCACUCUAACCUCUCCAGCUUAUCUAACAUGUCAUAAACAUAAUAAAUCUGUGUUGUCCAAU